GACAUGAUUGAGGUCUGCACACUAGUGAUGGGGGCUGGCACUUCAUCUCAUAACAUUGAAAGAAAAAGCAUUUCCCCCCUCAGUCUUUGUUGAAUUUCUCUGAUGCGUCUUGAUUUACGUUACUUCUGUGCCGGAAAACCUUCUUGCGCCUUCCGUCACCUUCAGGAUUAAGUUCAGAUUGGGCAUGCCAGUUUGCACAUGAUCUGGCCCUUGCCUACCUUUCCAGUUUAUCUUCCACUGUAUAUCCCUGCUUCCCCGCCUUCCCCCUCACGGCCUUACCUCUGUUCUCUGUAGCUGCCCUGCACCUGCCUGUUCACCCUGUUCCCUUUCCUGUGCUCUGAGUCGUGCAGUCAGUCCUUCAAGGCCCAUUGCAAGUCAUAUCUACAAAACAGGAGCCGCCUGGAUCCGCCCACUACCCCCAGGACUUGUCUCACCUUCCUCUGAUGGCCAUGGUACUGAAAGCGUCUGCUCUCAUCGUCCCCCUUUAUAGUCUAAACAUGUUUUCUGUCUGCUUCCACCGUCACUGAAUUACUCAUUUAUUUGUUAAUGUUUCAUCUCUCCAACUGGACUGCCAGAAAGUUGAGAUAUGGGCCCAAAUCUGAUUAAUGUUUGCAGUCCCCAAGCACAGUAGCUGUCAUGUAAGUCAGUAGCCCAUAAGGAUGAAUGAAUGAGCCUCCCGCCUGAUCUUUAUGUACACUGGCAUAUGUAUUGCCAGGCACUGAGACUGCAAGAAUCUAAAGAGAGAAACUAAAGAACGUAAAGAGAGAUGUUAAACUCUUAGAGUAAAAUUGGGACAAAUCAAAUGUAAUUGGAUGAGAUGAAUCUUUUGUAGAAGUAACUCACUCGGUGGCAGAGGAAUUUCUAGGAUCAUCCAAAACUUAGGGAGACCAGGGUAUAGUCUCAGUAAGGUAUAUGUCUGGUUAGAACAUAUCUAAAAUGUACCUAAGACUGAUUUUCAUGUGUCAAUAAGGAACUGUAAAGUGAGAGACUUAGGGUCAGAUAAGCUUGGAGACACCGCAUACUGUAUAGCAGUGAUCACAGUGCGAGUUUACUUGCUAAACACUCCCAGGAUUCUUGCGUUAAAUGACUUGGUUUAAUCAGCGUUUCUCUGAUUUAUAUCCAUAACACCCUUUUUGAGAAUCCCAUGUGCAUUUUGUUGAAACCAGGGAGCAUGCUUUUGGAAAUGCUGCAGCAGAGGAUGCAAAGAGCCUUUGGAGCGGGGAAGACUUCUGAGCAUUCUUCCUUCCCUGCCAAGUGUGUUCUUUCUUGCUCUGGGGAGGGGGUGGGGCGGGGGAAUGCUUCGAGCACAACUCCUUAGUUUUCUUGUUCCUUAGUUUAUUUUUAUCAUAAUUUGGCUUCACAUGGAACGUUCCUGAGGAGGAAAAUGUCCUGACCAUGCCAAAGUCAAAGAGUAAAAUGAAGUACAUUCUGGUUACUGGUGGUGUUAUAUCAGGAAUUGGAAAAGGAAUCAUUGCCAGCAGUGUGGGCACAAUACUCAAGUCAUGUGGUUUACAUGUAACUUCAAUCAAAAUUGACCCCUACAUUAACAUUGAUGCAGGAACAUUCUCUCCUUAUGAGCAUGGUGAGGUUUUUGUGCUGGAUGAUGGUGGGGAAGUAGACCUUGACCUGGGUAACUAUGAGCGGUUCCUUGACAUCCGCCUCACCAAGGACAAUAAUCUGACCACUGGAAAGAUAUACCAGUAUGUCAUUAACAAGGAACGGAAAGGAGAUUACUUGGGGAAAACUGUCCAAGUUGUCCCUCAUAUCACAGAUGCAAUCCAGGAGUGGGUGAUGAGACAGGCGUUAAUACCUGUAGAUGAAGAUGGCCUGGAACCUCAAGUGUGUGUUAUUGAGCUUGGUGGAACCGUGGGGGACAUAGAAAGCAUGCCCUUUAUUGAGGCCUUCCGUCAGUUCCAAUUCAAGGUCAAAAGAGAGAACUUUUGUAACAUCCACGUCAGUCUAGUUCCCCAGCCAAGUUCAACAGGGGAACAGAAGACUAAACCUACCCAGAAUAGUGUUCGGGAACUUAGAGGACUUGGGCUUUCCCCAGAUCUGGUUGUAUGCAGGUGCUCAAAUCCACUUGACACAUCAGUGAAGGAGAAAAUAUCAAUGUUCUGCCAUGUUGAGCCUGAACAAGUGAUCUGUGUCCACGAUGUCUCAUCCAUCUACCGAGUCCCCUUGUUGUUAGAGGAGCAAGGGGUUGUAGAUUAUUUUCUUCGAAGACUUGACCUUCCUAUUGAGAGGCAGCCAAGAAAAAUGCUGAUGAAAUGGAAAGAGAUGGCUGACAGAUAUGAUCGCUUGCUGGAGACCUGCUCUAUUGCCCUUGUGGGCAAAUACACGAAGUUCUCAGACUCCUAUGCCUCUGUCAUUAAGGCUCUGGAGCAUUCUGCACUGGCCAUCAACCACAAAUUGGAAAUCAAGUACAUAGAUUCUGCGGACUUGGAGCCCAUCACCUCGCAAGAAGAGCCCGUGCGCUACCACGAAGCUUGGCAGAAGCUCUGUAGUGCUCAUGGAGUGCUGGUUCCAGGAGGAUUUGGUGUUCGAGGAACAGAAGGAAAAAUCCAAGCAAUUGCCUGGGCUCGGAAUCAGAAAAAGCCUUUUUUGGGCGUGUGCUUAGGGAUGCAGUUGGCAGUGGUUGAAUUCUCAAGAAACGUGCUGGGAUGGCAAGAUGCCAAUUCUACAGAGUUUGACCCUACGACCAGUCAUCCCGUGGUCGUAGACAUGCCAGAACACAACCCAGGGCAGAUGGGCGGAACCAUGAGGCUGGGCAAGAGGAGAACCCUGUUCCAGACCAAGAACUCAGUCAUGAGGAAACUCUAUGGAGACGCAGACUACUUGGAAGAGAGGCACCGCCACCGAUUUGAGGUGAAUCCAGUCUGGAAAAAGUGUUUGGAAGAACAAGGCUUGAAGUUUGUUGGCCAAGAUGUUGAAGGAGAGAGAAUGGAAAUUGUGGAGUUAGAAGAUCAUCCCUUUUUUGUUGGGGUUCAGUACCACCCUGAGUUCCUGUCCAGGCCUAUCAAGCCCUCCCCACCAUACUUUGGCCUCCUCCUGGCCUCUGUGGGGCGGCUCUCACAUUACCUCCAGAAAGGCUGCAGGCUCUCACCCAGGGACACCUAUAGUGACAGGAGUGGAAGCAGCUCCCCUGACUCUGAAAUCACCGAACUGAAGUUUCCAUCAAUAAAUCAUGACUGAUCUUGUAGCGGAUGAUUCUUCAAGAGACCCUUCAAACUUGGGUAGAGUUUACAGCUCUGACUUUACACUCGGCUUUGGAGACUUUCUUUAAAUUAUGUUUUUAUUAAGAUUAUUUUAUUAUGCGGAAAGGUAUUUGGGAAACUUGUCACUUGCAUGUCCCAUCACGUGUACUGGCUCCUCUGUGGUGUCUGCCUGUUGCGUGACACUCUCCUUGCAGUUCUUGAGUUGCGGCAGAACAUCGCGAUGGGAACCGAUGGUGGGUGGGGCUGCAGAGUGCCCCAUCGGUCACCUUGUUUCUCAACUACCUCGCAUCAUUGCAGAUGCUAGCGCGUUGCCUGUCGCUUUCCCUUGGAUACCUAGACCGUUAUAAAGUGUGCCACAUGGACUUACCGAGCAUGGAGAGAGGAUUUUAGCUAGGAUUUGAACACUUGGUGCUGGGAACCUCAGGGUAUUGCUUGCCACUAAGCCAUGAAACCAGAGACAAAAUCUCUAUACUGCCCUGAGUUGGGGGGAAUUCUCAGUGCCAACUGUGGCUGGUCCUCAUUCAAAGGGACGGUCAGUUUGGUGUCAACAUGAAACACCAAGAUGUCUGUCUCUGAAGCGUGAUUUUAAAAUCCCCAUGCCUGUGGCUGCGCUUCCUAUUUCUAGGGCUGGGAAACACUCCUUGCAUCAAGGGGUCACUUACAGAACAAAGAAUCUUUUGGGGGAAACUUCCUCUAAAACCCUCUCAUAUAUAGACAGCUUUGACUGGAGGGUCCAUUUUUCUUCCAGGAUGGUGUUACUGCAGUUGAAAGGGCAAUAUGAAGUUACUUUCUUAAUGUGACCUAGCAAUAGGCAUAGCUACGUGGCACUAUAUUCUGGCCAGACUCGAUGUGUACUCUAACUUAAGAAAUAAAUCAGUAAGGCAGAACAAGAGA